UCACCCAGCCCCCACUCCCCAUUAGAUUUGCCAGAGGUUUUCAUGGUCUUUUCAAAGAAUAGACAUGCUUACUGUUCAAUAUAGGCAAAACCAGGCCACAGCUCAUCCUGCCAGGAGAAUCCACACCUACAGAGGGAUGCCGCACUCCAGCAGCCCUAUAGGAAAUUUCUUUCAAGAAACUUGCUUCACACCCGUGGCCAGAGUGCUAUGAAGAGAGGUCCUCUCUGGUUACGUUCAGUGCAGCAGUUGAAAGAGGAAAAGGGAGUAUGUUUUUAUGGAAACCUCAAAUGCCCUUCCACAUCUCCUGUGAAUUACCUCUGUGUUCAGGCAGCCGAGCUAGACAGCUGCGAGGAGAGGCGUGUGGUUUUGAUGGGGGCCUUGGAAAGAAAAGGCCCCUUGUACCCUGGCCAGCGCAUGUAGGUGGUGUGACCUGGGAGGACAGCGGAGCCAGGAGCUCCGCAGCUGUGUCAGAAGCCAGGCUCCCAGCGGCAAUGUUCCAGGGAGCCAAAGGGGGAGCCAGAGAGCCGGGAGGCUCCAGCCUGGUCCAGAGAGAAAGAGACAGCACCUGCCCAAGGCGAUUGUGUCCUGCAGUCUGAAAAACACUGACAUAGUAAAGCUCAACAAAUGUUUGGCUCCUUCACAAUCAGUGAAGAAUUAGGUACUUUCUUGCCAAAGAUAGCUGAAGCUCAAAGCCCGUACCAUAUGGACACUUGGGAUAUUUUGAGCAACCAUGUUGGGAUGCGGGCUAGUGGCAGCACCAACUGAUAACGUGGCUAUGGGAGCUAUUUUAAGUGUUCACCUACUCUCCCCAUCCCAUGCUCUCCCCAAAUGCCAAUGGUUCUCAACAUUUUUUGGAUCAUGGCCCCUUCAAGAAAUGGAUGGCUACCAAGGAUCCUCUUGUCAGAACAGCACAUGUCCCCAUAUCUGCCACAUUCUGCACUUUAUUUCAGAGGCUCUAUGGACUUCAGAAUUUGAACCCUAUUCCAGAUAUUCAGACUCAGAGACCUAGAGGUAUGUCUCUGCUGCCUGCCUCUUUCCUCUGAAACCAUGCCUUAAAAACACCAAGGGGACAUUGAAACCUGCUUUUCUGGAUCACAUUCUGAAAACUGCUGUUCAGAAGAGUUGCAGCUUCAACAGGGCCACAGGGAUAUAAAAGCAGCCCUGGAAUGAUGUCUUCCCUAAAAACAACAAAAUCAUCAAUAAUGAAUAGGAAGAACCAAUAUUGUGAAAAUGGCCAUACUGCCCAAAGCAAUUUAUAGAUUCAGUGCUAUUCCCAUUAAACUACCACUGACAUUCUUCACAGAAUUAGAAAAAACUAUUUUAAAAUUCAUAUAGAACCAAACAAGAGCUUGUAGAGCCAAGACAAUCCUAAGCAAAAAUAACAAAGCUAGAGGCAUCAUGCUACCCAACUUCAAACUAUACUACAAGGCUACAGUAACCAAAACAGCAUGGUAUGCUACAAAAACAGGCACAUAGACCAAUGAAACAGAAAGAGAACUUAGAAAUAAAACCACACAUCUACAACCAUCUGAUCUUCCGAAAACCUGACAAAAACAAGCAAUGGGGAAGGGAUUCCCUAUUUAAUAAAUGGUGCCAGGAGAACUGGCUAGCCAUAUGCACAAAAUUGAAACUGGCCCCUUCCUUACACCUUACACAAAAAUUAACACUAGAUGAAUUAAAGACUUAAACGUAAAACCAAAAACUAUAAAAACCCUAGAAGAAAAUCUAGGCAAUAACAUUCAGGACAUAGGCAUAGGAAAAGAUUUUAUGAAAUUGCCAAAAGCAAUUGCAACAAAAGCAAAAAUUGACAAAUGGGAUCGAAUUAAACUAAUGAGCUUCUGCACAGCAAAAGAAACUAUCAUCAGAGUGAACAGACAACCUAUAGAAUGGGAGAAAAUGUUUUCAAUCUAUCCAUCUGACAAAGGUCUAAUAUCCAGAAUCUACAAGGAACUUAAGCAAAUUUACGAAACCCCCCACAAACAACCCCAUUAAAAAGUGGGCAAAGAAUGUGAAUAGACACUUCUCAAAAGAAGACAUACAUGCAGCCAACAAAUACAUGAAAAAAGAGCUCAACAUUACUGAUCAUUAGAGAAAUGCAAAUUAAAACCACAAUGAGAUACCAUCUCAUGCCAGUCAGAAUGGCGAUUAUCAAAAAGUCAAGAAACAACAGAUGCUGGCGAGGUUGCGAAGAAAUAGCAACGUUUUUACGCUGUUGGUGGGAAUGUAAAUUAGUUCAACCAUUGUGGAAGACAGUAUAGCGAUUCCUCAAAGAUUUAGAACCAGAAAUACCAUUUGAUCCACAAUCCCAUUACUGGGAAUAUACCCAAAGGAAUAUAAAUAAUUCUAUUAUAAAGAUACAUGCAUGCAUAUGUUCAAUGCCGCACUAUUCACAAUAGCAGACUUGGAAUCAACCCAAAUGCCCAUCAAUGAUAGACUGGAUAAAGAAAAUGUGGUAUAUAUACACCAUGGAAUACCAUGCAGCCAUAAAAAGGAACAGGAUCAUAUCCUUUGCAGGGACAGGGAUGGAGCUGGAGGCAUUAUCCUCAGCAAACUGGCAAAGGAACAGAAAACCAAACACCGCAUGUUCUCACUUAUAAAUGGGAGCUGAACAGUGAGAACACAUGGACACAGGGAGGGGAACAACACAUAUUGGGGCCAGUUGGGGGAGUGCGGGGUGGAGAGAGCAUCAGGAAAAAUAGCUAAUGCAUGCCGGGCUUAAUACCUAGGUGAAGGAAGGGUUGAUAGGUGCAGCAAACCAGCAUGGCACAUGUUUACCUAUGUAACAAACCUGCAUAUCCUGCACAUGUAUCCCGGAACUUAAAAUUUUUAAAAAUCGUCAAUAAUAACAAUGAAAGCAGCUAACGUUUUUGGGUACUUGCUAUGUUCCAAACACCGAACUAAGCUCCUUACAUGCAUUAUCUCAUUUAAUACUCCCCAAACUUCCAUGAUGGCAAUAGUAUCCUGGUCCCUGUUUUGCAGAUGAGACACUAAGGCACACAGAGGUUAAAUAACUUGCCCAAGAUCACACAGCUAGUAAGUAGUAAGAUUCAAACCCAGACCCAGACCGUGCUGUCAAUCAGUAUACUUUGUGACCACCUAGUGACAUCACAGGAACCACACUUCCAUCACCUAUUUUAAUGCCCUGAAUGUUCAUCCUAAUAAAUGCACAUUAGACUUGAGUGGGUAAAAAUUCUGAAUGUACUGAGUCUUCUACCUUGGGCCAAUCCUUCUCUUCAAAAUGAACCUGCAUGGGAAUCAAUGCUGAAAGUGGAAAGAGACCCCAGACAGGCCUGGCAUCUGUAUGCAUAAGACAGAAAACCAUCUCCCUGCACCCCUACUCCCAGUUAAAAGGCUGUGGGCAUCUUUGAGCCAAUGAAUGGGCUGCUACAAAGAAUUCUGGGAAUCCCAACCCCUCACAGUUCUGCAACUCACAGUCCUGCAAAAGGUGGGUACUAGAAUAGGGAGGUGGGCAUAUAGGCCAAAUACUCUGUUCUGCCUUCCAGGAGGGAAAAAGCAUGCUACCCAGGAAGCUCACAAGUGACAUGUGGCCCAUGGGCAUACCAGGGCUAAAGUGAAGGAUGGACUGCUCUGUGGAAGGAAGGAGUGAAAGUGAACAAGAGGCAUAGGGCCACCUGCAGGAAGACUGAGAGGAGGGAAGGAGGAAGGCUGGCUUUGGCAGGGAGGGGAGGCAGGAGCAGAGGGAGCCAGAGGAUCGGUUCAGGCAGUGAGAGAGGGCAGCCCCACUCUAUUUCCCAGGCUGCUCUCUGGAUGCAGGCAGGAAGGUUGAGUGUAUUACACUGGCCCCACCUCCAGAGGCUCUCUCUGCAGCCGCUGGACUGGACACAAAGCGUGAGAGACAGAGACACCAUCUCUGCUGAUUUGUACCUAACUGGUUCCUGUUGCUGAGAGCCCACGUGUCACAGAAGCCAGGGCAGAGGCCCCACACUGCUGUCUGCAUUUCCCAGGUAUCCUGAGCCAAGCAGGAUACUCCUCCUCAGAGGAGUAGGCAAUAGAAGCGCCUGAACAUCAUGGCACAAGUGGACUCCCAGGACAGGUGGGGAGAGGCGUCUCCUCUCAGCAGCUUGACUGAGGAAGCUCAUGACACCCAGAUGCUGAGCAUGAACUUAGAGAGUGACGAUGAAGAUGGUGGGGAGGCCGAAAAAGAGGGCACCGCUGACCCGGUGGCCUGUCCAAGGGGCAGCUCCCCAGUAACACACGAAAAUCCUGACUUGCCAUGGCCCCAUCCACUGGGCAAAGAGGAAGAGAAAUUCUCUGACUCCUCCAGUGCUGGGGGCAUGGGGCAGAAACCAGUGGAAAUGUCUGGGAAAGCCAGUUGGAGCAGAGAUGUGACAAAGAUCAACGAGACCCAGGGUUCCCCGGGAGCAAGCAGAGCUCUGGGUUCCCUUCCCAGUGGUCUCGCACACAAAUUGUUAGGUCAGAUGCAACCUCUUGGGGACCGACUACCUGCGGGUGAUGAUGGAUACUCGGGGGCAAACCAGGACGCAGUCUUGGAUGUCCCACCCAGCUUCCCCAGCAAUGGAAAGUAUCUCUGUGCGCACAAAAGUGUAGACACGUCCGCAGGGAACUCUUCUCUGUUGUGUUUCCCCAGGCCGGGGAGCAACUGGGACCUUCCCACGCAAGAGACACAUACACCAGCCCAGGCGUCGGCCACCCCAGCCAGCCUGGCUGCCGCGGUCCUGGCAAAAGCGCGGAACAGCAGGAAAGUACAGAACCAGGCGGGCCGGCGCGAGGGCGGAGAGGCUGAGGCGCGUCCCUACAGGUGCCUGCGGGGCGGGCGGGCCUUUCAGAAGCCCAGCAAGCCGCUGAGCCCCGCGGAGACGCGCGGCGGCGCCGCCAAGCGCUACGCGUGCGAGCUAUGCGGGAAGGCCUACUCCCACCGCGGCACACUCCAGCAGCACAGGCGCCUGCACACGGGCGAGCGGCCCUACCAGUGCUCCUUCUGCGACAAGGCCUACACCUGGUCCUCCGACCACCGGAAGCACAUCCGCACCCACACAGGCGAGAAACCCUACCCGUGUCCAGACUGCGGGAAGGCCUUCGUGCGCUCUUCGGACCUGCGCAAACACCAGCGCAACAUGCACAGCAACAAUAAGCCCUUCCCGUGCUCCGAGUGCGGCCUGACCUUCAACAAGCCGCUGUCGCUGCUGCGCCACCAGCGCACGCACCUGGGCGCCAAGCCCUUCCGCUGCCCCGCCUGCGACCGGGAGUUCGCUGUGGCCAGCCGCAUGGUGGAGCACCAGCGCGUGCACUCGGGCGAGCGGCCCUUCCCCUGCCCCACCUGCGGCAAGUGCUUCACCAAGUCCUCCAAUCUGUCCGAGCACCAGACGCUGCACACCGGCCAGAGGCCUUUCAAGUGCGCUGACUGCGGCGUGGCCUUCGCGCAGCCCUCGCGCCUCGUGCGCCACCAGCGCAUCCACACUGGCGAGAGGCCCUUUCCUUGCACGCAGUGUGGCCAGGCCUUUGCCCGCUCUUCGACCCUGAAGCGGCACCAACAGAUCCACUCCGGGGAGAAGGGAUUCCUCUGUGCCGAGUGCGGCAGGGCCUUCCGCAUUGCCUCUGAGUUGGCCCAGCACAUACGAAUGCACAACGGAGAGAGGCCCUACCAGUGUGAGGACUGCGGCCAGGCCUUCACCAGGUCCAAUCACCUCCAACGACACCGAGCCAAGCACGGCACCUGCAAGAAGGAGCCCAUCCCUUCCUCCUCUGACGAGUGAAGAUAGCAUCGUCGACCUCACUACUUGGAACCUUCCCAGGUGGGCCCACUCACAUGGUAUUGCCAGCCUCACUGGUCAGCCUCGCCUCCCAGCAGGUCGCGGGUCAUCAGUGGUCCAUUUGAUUAUUUAUUUGAUCCCUUGAACAGAAAGUCACCACCGAGAGAGCACCCAGGUGGGUGGUUUCACAUCAGUGGUUCUGAGUGUCCGAGGUCAUAAGCAAUUGGAAAAGGGAAAGACAAAGUAGUGGGAGCUGAUCAAACGUUGAGUUCCUUGGGUUGGGGAACCUGAAUCAAUCAGAAACUGCUUCUAGAAUUACAUGCUGGGCACUGGGCCGGGCUCCAGGGAUAAGGUGGGGAAAAAGACUAACCUGUCCUACCCUCAAAGCCAUAUGCAAAUACUGAAAAGAAGGCCUGAGGGGCUGGUCCUCUUUAGAGAAAGAUGCUUUUUGGUUUUUAUAUAAAUAAAGGAAUCCCCAGAAGUGGUCCCUAUGAUGAACUCCCCCAAAGCAACGCCGUUUUUGGAGGAACUCAAACCCAGUCCAACAUCCCAUCAUUUCACUUGACUGCAGAAAUGGCUUUACCCUUAGGAUAUAUCUUUAUGAGUCUUGGCUUUGAAGUGGAGAAGGGCUUUAUCUUAGAGAAGGUGGUUUAUGUCAUAUUCCAGUUAUUCUAGAAGUUCAGGACAGCCUUAGCAUCUGAAAAAGAAGCCCAUUCCUCUUUAUAGUGGAAUUUAGUAAGUAGAUCUAACCCGAGUCUCACCCACAGAAUUCAUAUAAAUUCAUAUAUGCCUUCUCUCUGGCUGCCUCUUUUCCUGUUUGCACUCUGAGGGCUUAAGUCAUAUGUGAUAUUUACAAAGCAAUUGGCCCAUUUACAGAGAGACAUAUAUAAUUUCUCCACAAAGCCUUGACCAUGGUUCAUGAAACCGUUUGGGUUCAUUUAAAUUUGUCUGAAUCAUUAGUCUUGACUUGAAGUGAACAAAACACCCUUUGCCCAAGUGCCAUUGGCUUGUCUGCAUUUCAAAAUCAUUAAAACCAGGUAUGGAAGCCUACGUGCUCACAGUUAUCUAAUGAGGUUAUUUCAAAGUUUGCAUUACUAACAGCCAUUCUGCAAAGUGUAUUGAUGUGUAUAGUGAUCUGUAUAAAGUCAGUAGUUCUUAGCUGAACCUCAACUGUGAGGAAUCUAUGACUCCACAGAUGUCCUUGGUGCACAUAGGCAAACGGCACUUCUCAUCUUACUGAAGUUAAAUAAGAUAUUCCAUAAGAAGGUAUAGUGCCCUUUUUGGGGGAGUACCUUUAGUAUAUUCCUAAAAUUGCCACCAAAGAAUGCCAAAUCUGAAUUUCUCUUGGUUUCCACCUGAUUUGGAACUAGGGUGUGACCUCUAAAUAGCAUUCUCAUGACACAUGGGGGCGCCAAAGAGAAGUAAGAGAGAUAGCUAGAUAGCUAGAUAGCUAGAUAGUCUUGUGUCUUGUUUGACCAAGGUAACCGUAAUAAAAGAGUCCAUCCCCAUCCUUUACUGUUGAUGUGACCUUGGGCUUCAGUUUCUGCAUCUGCAUUGGCAAAAUAGAAGUGAUAGUAGUAGGUAAAAGUUAGAGUGAUCCUACUAUAUGACGGAAACUUUGGCUGGAUGCAAGAGCUUUAAAUUGGUAGAAAAGUCACAAGAUGAGCUUGUGACUAUGAAGAGAGCAAAAGCUAACUUUUUUUUCCUAGAUAAUCAAUAAAAUAUUUGAAGACUGAA